CACUUCCGCUUCCGCUGGGGAGGUCCUCCAUGCGCAGUCAUGAGUCGCUUCAAGUUUAUCGGUAAGAGGAGCGUUUUCCACGCCCUUGGGUCUUUCUGACUUGUCCCGGGCGUCGGUCACCAAGGUCACAGGACCCAGGAAUUGCGCCCUCCGGCAUUAUAUUGGUAUCAACUUGACUGACCCUAUGUUCAGAGGAAUUUAUAGGGGGGUUCAAAAGCAUCAAGAUGACUUACAGGAUGUAAUAGGGAGAGCUGUCGAGAUUGGUGUUAAAAAGUUUAUGAUUACAGGUGGAAAUCUACAAGACAGUAAAGAUGCACUGCAUUUGGCACAAACAAAUGGUAUGUUUUUCAGUACAGUUGGAUGUCAUCCUACAAGAUGUGGUGAAUUUGAAAAGAAUAACCCUGAUCUUUACUUAAAGGAGUUGCUAAAUCUUGCUGAAAACAAUAAAGGGAAAGUUGUGGCAAUAGGAGAAUGCGGACUUGAUUUUGACCGACUGCAGUUUUGUCCCAAAGAUACUCAACUCAAAUAUUUUGAAAAACAGUUUGAACUGUCAGAACAAACAAAAUUACCAAUGUUUCUUCAUUGUCGAAACUCACAUGCUGAAUUUUUGGACAUAAUGAAAAGAAAUAGAGAUCGGUGUGUAGGGGGAGUGGUGCAUUCAUUUGAUGGUACCAAGGAAGCAGCAGCUGCUUUGAUUGACUUGGAUCUUUAUAUAGGAUUUAAUGCAUUAUGUAUACAUAUACACGUCAUAUCUGACUAUGGACGAACGGUUUAUUCUGUGACAGUCAUACAUCUCUGCAGUCAAAGAAACCGAGGCUCAAAGAAAUUAGGAAACAGCUCACUGAAAACUGAAGCUAAUUUGGAAGUUUUGAAGUCAAUUCCUAGUGAAAAAUUAAUGAUUGAGACAGAUGCACCUUGGUGUGGAGUCAAAAGUACACAUGCUGGAUCAAAAUAUAUAAGAACUGCAUUUCCUACCAAAAAGAAGUGGGAAAGUGGGCACUGCUUAAAAGACAGAAAUGAACCCUGCCAUAUAAUUCAAAUAUUGGAGAUAAUGUCAGCAGUGAGAGAUGAGGAUCCACUGGAAUUAGCCAAUACACUAUAUAACAAUACUAUUAAAGUAUUUUUUCCUGGAAUAUAAUUGGUAUAUGUCUUCCACUUUCCAUCAUGUAUGUAAAAUUUCAUAGUAAAACUUCCUGAUAGUUUCAAUAAAGAAAUUAUCUGCAAGUUGUCUAAAGAAA